GCGGCUCGGUUCUCCCGCCUCCGCCUCCGCCGCGGCUCGUGGUUGUCCCGCCAUGGCACUGUCGCGGGGGCUGCCCCGGGAGCUGGCUGAGGCGGUGGCCGGGGGCCGGGUGCUGGUGGUGGGGGCGGGCGGCAUCGGCUGCGAGCUCCUCAAGAAUCUCGUGCUCACCGGUUUCUCCCACAUCGACCUGCCACCAGGGUCUCACUAUUUUGCUUAGGCUGGUCUUGAAGGUCUGGGCUCAAGCGAUUCUCUCACUUUGUCCUCCCAAAGUGUUGGGAUUACAGAUUGAUCUGGAUACUAUUGAUGUAAGCAACCUCAACAGACAGUUUUUGUUUCAAAAGAAACAUGUUGGAAGAUCAAAGGCACAGGUUGCCAAGGAAAGUGUACUGCAGUUUUACCCGAAAGCUAAUAUCGUUGCCUACCAUGACAGCAUCAUGAACCCUGACUAUAAUGUGGAAUUUUUCCGACAGUUUAUACUGGUUAUGAAUGCUUUAGAUAACAGAGCUGCCCGAAACCAUGUUAAUAGAAUGUGCCUGGCAGCUGAUGUUCCUCUUAUUGAAAGUGGAACAGCUGGGUAUCUUGGACAAGUAACUACUAUCAAAAAGGGUGUGACCGAGUGUUAUGAGUGUCAUCCUAAGCCGACCCAGAGAACCUUUCCUGGCUGUACAAUUCGUAACACACCUUCAGAACCUAUACAUUGCAUCGUUUGGGCAAAGUACUUGUUCAACCAGUUGUUUGGGGAAGAAGAUGCUGAUCAAGAAGUAUCUCCUGACAGAGCUGACCCUGAAGCUGCCUGGGAACCAACGGAAGCCGAAGCCAGAGCUAGAGCAUCUAAUGAAGAUGGUGACAUUAAACGUAUUUCUACUAAGGAAUGGGCUAAAUCAACUGGAUAUGAUCCAGUUAAACUUUUUACCAAGCUUUUUAAAGAUGACAUCAGGUAUCUGUUGACAAUGGACAAACUAUGGCGGAAAAGGAAACCUCCAGUUCCGUUGGACUGGGCUGAAGUACAAAGUCAAGGAGAAGAAACGAAUGCAUCAGAUCAACAGAAUGAACCCCAGUUAGGCCUGAAAGACCAGCAGGUUCUAGAUGUAAAGAGCUAUGCACGUCUUUUUUCAAAGAGCAUCGAGACUUUGAGAGUUCAUUUAGCAGAAAAGGGGGAUGGAGCUGAGCUCAUAUGGGAUAAGGAUGACCCAUCUGCAAUGGAUUUUGUCACCUCUGCUGCAAACCUCAGGAUGCAUAUUUUCAGUAUGAAUAUGAAGAGUAGAUUUGAUAUCAAAUCAAUGGCAGGGAACAUUAUUCCUGCUAUUGCUACUACUAAUGCAGUAAUUGCUGGGUUGAUAGUAUUGGAAGGAUUGAAGAUUUUAUCAGGAAAAAUAGACCAGUGCAGAACAAUUUUUUUGAAUAAACAACCAAACCCAAGAAAGAAGCUUCUUGUGCCUUGUGCACUGGAUCCUCCCAACCCCAAUUGUUAUGUAUGUGCCAGCAAGCCAGAGGUGACUGUGCGGCUGAAUGUCCAUAAAGUGACUGUUCUCACCUUACAAGACAAGAUAGUGAAAGAAAAAUUUGCUAUGGUAGCACCAGAUGUCCAAAUUGAAGAUGGGAAAGGAACAAUCCUAAUAUCUUCCGAAGAGGGAGAGACGGAAGCUAAUAAUCACAAGAAGUUGUCAGAAUUUGGAAUUAGAAAUGGCAGCCGGCUUCAAGCAGAUGACUUCCUCCAGGACUAUACUUUAUUGAUCAACAUCCUUCAUAGUGAAGACCUAGGAAAGGACGUUGAAUUUGAAGUUGUUGGUGAUGCCCCGGAAAAAGUGGGGCCCAAACAAGCUGAAGAUGCUGCCAAAAGCAUAACCAAUGGCAGUGAUGAUGGAGCUCAGCCCUCCACCUCCACAGCUCAAGAGCAAGAUGACGUUCUCAUAGUUGAUUCAGAUGAAGAAGAUUCUUCAAAUAAUGCCGACGUCAGUGAAGAAGAGAGAAGCCGCAAGAGGAAAUUAGAUGAGAAAGAGAAUCUCAGUGCAAAGAGGUCACGUAUAGAACAGAAGGAAGAGCUUGAUGAUGUCAUAGCAUUAGAUUGAACAGAAAUGCCUCUAAACAGAACCCUCUUACUAUUUAGUUUAUCUGGGCAGAACCAGAUUGUUAUGUCCUUUGUUCCAAAGGGAAAAAAUUGACAGCAGUGACUUGAAAAUGAUUCUGCUCCCUUUGAAAGCAUUCAUUUUGCUAGAACUGUUAGACACAUUGCAGUAUGCUGUAUUGAAAGUAGGAAUAUAGUUUUAAAAACCCUUUGAACAAAGUGUGUGCAUAACCAGUCAUGAGAUAAAACAACACAAUGCAUGUUGCCUUUUUAAUGUAAAUACCCGUAGGUAUCAUUAAUAGUUUCAAAAUAUUGUGGUUUAGUAAAGUUGAUACCUGGUUAUAAAUAUUAUGCCUUUAUUUUUGGCUAGAAGAAGAAUUAUUUUUAGCCUAGAUCUAACCAUUUUCAUACUCUUAACUGAUUGAAACAGAUUCAAAGAAGUAUCGAGUGCUAUGCAUUGAAACUUGUUUUUAAAUGUUAGAUGGCACUAUGUAUAUUAAUGUAAAACAAUGUUAAUUUACUCAAGUUUUCAGUUUGUACCGCCUGGUAUGUCUGUGUAAGAAGCCAAUUUUUGUGUAUUGUUACAGUUUCAGGUUAUUUAUAUUCGAUGUUUUGUAAAACUCAAAUAACGACUAUACUUAUGGACCAAAUAAAUGGCAUCUGCAUUCUUGUUACACAUGCCUGCACAGUUCCUGUUUCUGCUGCCUUAUAUCUACUGCAGGAAUGUCAAAUUCUUUUCAUUAAAAAAAGAACUCGGUCGGGCACGGUGGCUCAUGCCUGUAAUCCCAGCACUUUGGAAGGCUGAGGCAGGUGGAUCACCUGAGGUCAGUAGUUCAAGACCAACCUGGUCAACAUGGUGAAACCCCAUCUCUACUAAAAAAAAAAAAAAAAAUUAGCCGGGCCUGGUGGCAGGCACCUGUAAUUCCAGCUACUCAGGAGGCUAAGGCAGCAGAAUUGCUUGAACCCGGGAGGCAGAGGUUGCAGUGAGCCAAGAUUGUGCUAUUGCUACUCCAGCCAGGGCGAUGAGUGAAACUCCAUCUCAAAAAAGGUUCAGAAGAUCUCCACUGUUUGCCAAAGACGAGUACUUUCUUUUCUUUAUUCUUGGAGACUUCACAUGUAGGAAGAGUACUUUCUAAAAUAAAGCUCUUCCUGCGUGUGGUGGUGGUGCACAUCUGUGUUCCAGCUACUCAGGAGGCUGAGGCAGGAGGAUGGCUGGAGCCCAGAAGUUCAAGGCCAGCCUGGGUAACAUAGCAAGACCCUGUCUCUAAAAAAUAAGUAAAUAAAAUAAAGCUUUUAAUGGCAGUGGGUUUUUUGUUCGUUUUUGAGAUGAAGCCUCACACUGUCAUCUGGCCUGGAGUGCAGUGGCGCGAUCCUGGCUCACUGCAGCCUCCGCCUUCCAGGUGCAAGCGAUUCUCCUGUCUCAGCCUCCCCUGUAGCUGGGAUUACAGGCGCCCUCCACCACGCUCAGCUAAUUUUUUGUAUUUUUAGUAGAGAUGGGGUUUCACUAUGUUGGCCAGGCUGGUCUGGAACUCCUGACCUCGUGAUCCACCUGCCUCAGCCUCCCAAAGUGCUGGGAUUACAGGCGUGAGCCACUGCGCCUGGCCUAAUGGCAGUGUUUUUAAAAUUUGGAUUGUCAGCAGUUGGCCUUUGUUGAGAAAAUGUGUGACUUUGCCCAAGCCCAGUAACUUGGAGCCUUGAAUUUGAGAUGCUGGAAAGGGAGUCCUUCCUCCUUUCUGCAGUGUUUGUCUGGGUUGUCCCCUAGUUUACCAAAGUCCAUUUUGAAUGUACCAUCCCCAGCCCAACUCCAGCCUACAGAUAGUGCCAGACCGCCAGUAGGUGGAGUAGCACUGUCUUCCUGGUCCCGGACCUCAGAGGGCUUUGCCUGUUAGGGUACUCUUAUCACUCAGAGAUGGGCCUUGAGUUUUCAGAGAACAGAAAGCCAUUAAGCUGUUUCCCCUAUUGUAUUCAUGUGCCCUUUGUGUUUCUGGCAAUAAUUUAUUUUAUAUUUCAACUAAAUUUUAAAUUUCUAAUUCA